GACAGCAGCCACACCUCUGCAGAGAGAAUGGCCAGCAGGAAGGCGGGGACCCGGGGCAAGGUGGCAGCCACCAAGCAGGCCCAACGUGGUUCUUCCAACGUCUUUUCCAUGUUUGAACAAGCCCAGAUACAGGAGUUCAAAGAAGUCUCUCCCCCACCUCCCACCUUCCCUAGAGCUGGGGGCUGCUCCCACCUGAAGGCCCCCAUCCCACAGGCCUUCAGCUGUAUCGACCAGAAUCGUGAUGGCAUCAUCUGCAAGGCAGACCUGAGGGAGACCUACUCCCAGCUGGGGAAGGUGAGUGUCCCAGAGGAGGAGCUGGACGCCAUGCUGCAAGAGGGCAAGGGCCCCAUCAACUUCACCGUCUUCCUCACGCUCUUUGGGGAGAAGCUCAAUGGGACAGACCCCGAGGAAGCCAUCCUGAGUGCCUUCCGCAUGUUUGACCCCAGCGGCAAAGGGGUGGUGAACAAGGAUGAGUUCAAGCAGCUUCUCCUGACCCAGGCAGACAAGUUCUCUCCAGCUGAGGUGAGGCUGCCCAGCCCCUUCAAUACUCAUCCCCAGCACCUUCUCUGGGCCUUCACCCAUGACCCAGAGCCCAGUACCAGUGAGGCAGUUGCUGGAAGGGUGGAGCAGAUGUUCGCCCUGACACCCAUGGACCUGGCGGGGAACAUCGACUACAAGUCACUGUGCUACAUCAUCACCCAUGGAGACGAGAAAGAGGAAUGAGGGGCAGGGCCAGGCCCACGGGGGGGCACCUCAAUAAACUCUGUUGCAAAAUUGGAA